AGUCGCGGCGGAGCGCGGCGUUGGCGGCGGAUGGAGGGCGCGAGCGGGCGGCCGCGGAGGCUGCACCCGGCGGGGCGCUGAUGCGGCGCCUGGACCUUCGCUGCGCGACUUCGGGGGCGUCGGCCGAGUUGGGACUCCGCGAUGCAGCUCCUGAAGGCGCUCUGGGCACUGGCAGGGGCCGCGCUCUGCUGCUUCCUCGUCCUAGUGAUCCACGCGCAGUUCCUCAAAGAAGGUCAGCUGGCCGCCGGCACCUGUGAGAUUGUGACCUUGGACCGGGACAGCAGCCAGCCUCGGAGGACGAUCGCCCGGCAGACCGCCCGCUGUGCGUGUAGAAAGGGGCAGAUCGCCGGCACCACGAGAGCCCGGCCCGCCUGUGUGGACGCAAGAAUCAUCAAGACCAAGCAGUGGUGUGACAUGCUUCCGUGUCUGGAGGGGGAAGGCUGCGACUUGUUAAUCAACCGGUCAGGCUGGACGUGCACGCAGCCCGGCGGGAGGAUAAAGACCACCACGGUCUCCUGACAAACACAGCCCCUGAGGGGCCCCGGGAGUGGCCUUGGCUCCCUGGAGAGCCCACGUCUCAGCCACAGUUCUCCACUCGCCUCGGACUUCACCCGUUCUCUGCCGCCCGCCCACUCCGUUUCCCUGUGGUCCGUGAAGGACGGCCUCAGGCCUUGGCAUCCUGAGCUUCGGUCUGUCCAGCCGACCCGAGGAGGCCGGACUCAGACACAUAGGCGGGGGGCGGCACCUGGCAUCAGCAAUACGCAGUCUGUGGGAGCCCGGCCGCGCCCAGCCCCCGCCGACCGUGGCGUUGGCCCUGCUGUCCUCAGAGGAGGAGGAGGAGGAGGCAGCUCCGGCAGCCACAGAAGGCUGCAGCCCAGCCCGCCUGAGACACGACGCCUGCCCCAGGGGACUGUCAGGCACAGAAGCGGCCUCCUCCCGUGCCCCAGACUGUCCGAAUUGCUUUUAUUUUCUUAUACUUUCAGUAUACUCCAUAGACCAAAGAGCAAAAUCUAUCUGAACCUGGACGCACCCUCACUGUCAGGGUCCCUGGGGUCGCUUGUGCGGGCGGGAGGGCAAUGGUGGCAGAGACAUGCUGGUGGCCCCGGCGGAGCGGAGAGGGCGGCCGUGGUGGAGGCCUCCACCCCAGGAGCACCCCGCGCACCCUCGGAGGACGGGCUUCGGCUGCGCGGAGGCCGUGGCACACCUGCGGGAGGCAGCGACGGCCCCCACGCAGACGCCGGGAACGCAGGCCGCUUUAUUCCUCUGUACUUAGAUCAACUUGACCGUACUAAAAUCCCUUUCUGUUUUAACCAGUUAAACAUGCCUCUUCUACAGCUCCAUUUUUGAUAGUUGGAUAAUCCAGUAUCUGCCAAGAGCAUGUUGGGUCUCCCGUGACUGCUGCCUCAUCGAUACCCCAUUUAGCUCCAGAAAGCAAAGAAAACUCGAGUAACACUUGUUUGAAAGAGAUCAUUAAAUGUAUUUUGCAAAGCCUAAAGUUAUAUAUUUAACAGUUUUUAUAUGUUGUAUAUUUGUAGAAAAUCCUAUUUAACAAUUAACGUGGCAGUCCCGGCCGUCCUGAGAGUCGGGCCGAGCCCCGUGUGUUUCUGAAGACUCUGGGGGUGGGACACGGCGGGGAGGUGGUGCCCCGCGGACCCCGGGGUGCCAGGCACGGAAGGCGGGACUCUGGGAGAAGCGUGCGGAGGACCGUGGCGUCGGCGUCCCGGAUGUGUCGGUCGUGCCCGGGGAGGCCGGGUUCCCCUCGCUGCGGGCCAGGCUUGGCUCCUGAUUCCCUCUCUGGUCCCUGUAUUGGUCAACACUUGAGCGUACAAUAUCUUGAACAUGCUUCUUCCAAUGGGUUUUGUUUCCCAUUUCCUGCCCCUUUCGCCACUCACGGACCUUGAGGCCAGUUGACGGCCCUUCUCCCCACGCCUGUGUCCCCGCGUUCUGAGAAGUCCUCUGUCUUCGUGUCACUAGGUCCAGAAAGUCGCGCCGGGCAGAGGCGCAGGCGGGGCCGGCAGGGCCGAGGAAUAAGCGACAAUUCUGGUUUUUCUCCCCUGGCCGUCGUUCGCCAGCCUCCUUCAUUUUCCUGAGUUCCCGCUGAAGUAUAUACUACCUAUGAGUCCAAUUAACAUGAGUAUUAUGCUAGUUCUAUCCUACUAAAAAAAACGUAAAAAAAUAACUAUAUAGAAGCUGUUCCAGCAACCAUAGACUGAAGAUACGAAAGAAAAUCCAUUUAUUUAAGACCUGUUCCGGUAUCCAUGAGGACAUAAUUUACCUUUCAGUCACCACAAAUUUAUAGGCAUUUGUAUCCUGGACUAAAAGAAGGGGCUGAGGUUGGGUUUGUCAUCACAGAGGGGGUGGGCCUGGAAAGGGUCCUUCCCAAGCUGCCCCGGCUCCGGCGGCCCGGGCCGGCAGCCUCUGCCAGCCAGCGUCCUCACGGCCUCCCCCUCGCCUGUUUCUUUUGAAAGCAAGUGUAGACACCUUCGAGGGCAGAGAUCGGGAGAUUUAAGAUGUUACAGCAUAUUUUUUUUUCUUGUUUUACAGUAUUCAAUUUUGUGUUGAUUCAGCUAAAUUAUGAAAAAUAAAGAAAAACUCCUUUGAUAA